CUUCGGAUGUGGCUUGAGCUGUAGGCGCGGAGGGCCGGAGACGCUGCAGACCCGCGACCCGGAGCAGCUCGGAGGCGGUGAAGUCGGUGGCUUUCCUUCUCUCUAGCUCUCGCUCGCUGGUGGUGCUUCAGAUGCCACACGCGUCCCGGGGGCCCGGUUCUCCGCUCCCCUCCCCUCCCCUUCUCGCCGGACCCCGCGCCGGGAGCUGCGGGAAGGAGUGGAGGGUCGGGCGGUGGCCUCGCGGCUGGCCUGGCGCGCGGCCAGCGCCGGUAGUUAGUGGGGGGACUGCUCUGCCCUCGAGGGGGUAGGGAGCUGUGGCGACGGUUGCCCCAUUUCGAGACAAAGCGCAUUUCCCCCUCCCCUCCCCCACCCGCGUUCCGGCGGAGGCGCCCCCUCCCCCAGCCGCCACGCGGGGCUGGGUCGAGACUUGGGCCUCCCGGAGGGCGGCGCGUGGUCCCGCGUCCGCGAGGCCUGGCGGCGCGCGGCCGGCUGUCCCGAGGCUGCGGCGACCGCCCAGUUAACGUGGCCGCCGCGGGGGUAGGCGCGUGCGGUGUGGCGCAGUGCCCUUGAGCCCCCGUGCCGCGGCCUUUGUUUCUCCCCGCGGAUGCGCUGACCACGAGGCCCGCGCUCCCGGGUGGGGGCGGGCACCCGCGCUUAGGCCUCUGGACGCCGGGCUUCAGCGGCGGGGGUCGGGAGCGGGUGUUUGCAAGAGGUGAUUCUUUUUUCAAAGUGUCACGAAACGGGGUUGAAGCAUCUUAAGUUUUUUCCUUUUGUUAUUUAAUUACCGAUUGGAAAGAGGGAGGGUUUCUGAGCAGAAACCAAGUUGGGAUUGCAGAACAGAGAAGAUUCACAGUGCUUUACCGUUUAAUAGCUCUUCAAGUCUGCAAUAAAAAAUGGCCUCCAACAAAACUACAUUGCAAAAAAUGGGAAAAAAACAGAAUGGAAAGAGUAAAAAAGUUGAAGAGGCAGAGCCUGAAGAAUUUGUCGUGGAAAAAGUACUAGAUCGACGUGUAGUGAAUGGGAAAGUGGAAUAUUUCCUGAAGUGGAAGGGAUUUACAGAUGCUGACAAUACUUGGGAACCUGAAGAAAAUUUAGAUUGUCCAGAAUUGAUUGAAGCGUUUCUUAACUCUCAGAAAGCUGGCAAAGAAAAAGAUGGUACAAAAAGAAAAUCUUUAUCUGACAGUGAAUCUGAUGACAGCAAAUCAAAGAAGAAAAGAGAUGCUGCUGACAAACCAAGAGGAUUUGCCAGAGGUCUUGAUCCUGAAAGAAUAAUUGGUGCCACAGACAGCAGUGGAGAAUUGAUGUUUCUCAUGAAAUGGAAAGAUUCAGAUGAGGCAGACUUGGUGCUGGCGAAAGAGGCAAAUAUGAAGUGUCCUCAAAUUGUAAUUGCUUUUUAUGAAGAGAGACUAACUUGGCAUUCUUGUCCAGAAGAUGAAGCUCAAUAAUUGUUCACAUUGUUCUUUUAUAUAUAUUUAUAUAUAUAUAUAAAAAUUGGGUCUUAGAUUUUGAUUUACUAGUGUGACAAAAUAACUACAUCCUAAUGAAAAUCAAGUUUGAUAUGUUUGUUUUGAAAGUAGCGUUGGAAGAGUUGUUGGGGGUUUUUUGCAUCCAUAGCACUGGUUACUUUGAACAAAUAAAUAAAAGCUUUCUGUAGUUGCUUCCUUUAUCAGAAAAGAACAUUUGAUACCAUGGUAUAUCAUUUCCUCUUCAUUAAAGAACAGCUUUUCUAAAUGUUGGGGGAAAUGUCCAUAGUCAUUACUCAGUCAAAACUUGUGUUCUCAUGAGCCUAAGGACCAUUCUAGAUUUAUUACGUGUUUUUUGUGUGUGUGUGUGUGUGUGUGUGUGUGUGUAUCCAUAAAAUGCAUAUGUAAAUUUUUUUUUGUUUUUAAGCAUUCACCCAAACAAAAAAAUCACAGGUAAACCCAUGUUUCUGAGAUGCCAUUAUUCCAAGCAAAAUAAGAGAUAAUCCCUUCAAGUUAAAUUGAAAAUUUUCCUGAAACCAUACAUUUCAAGUGAAAUAAGUAAUUCUAGAUAGGACAAUUUAAAUUGGAUAAUUUUAAAGUGUCUAUAAUUGCAGUGGUUUAUUUGCAAAAUUCCUAAAAGGAAAAAUUUUAUCACUGCCAUCACAGCAGGUUUCCUCAUCCAGAUGAGGAAACUAGACAAAUGCUAGUGUGUUUUAACUAGCUAAACAAAACUAAGUUAAAUGAACAUUUAAAAGUUUCCCUAGCGGGCCAUUCCUUAGCAAAAUGUUGGAAUCCCUGUUGCUACAUUGACUAAAAGGUCAUGAUGAAUGGAAUAUGUAAGACUUGGCUCAUAGAAACCUAAUCAGAUGGUUAGAGGUGUUGGCAGUUUAGGACCUGCUGUCAUAAAUGUGUGAACAACCUUUUGUAACCUAACCUAUUGACCUGCAUGUUUUUUCUUUACCCCAAUUCAUUACAUGGAGGCUCAAUCUUGAGUUUGCUUUACUGGUUCAGCAAAAGCCAGGAAGAACAACUUUGUAGUAAUCAAAAUGUUAUCCAACUGUAUAUUGUUUACUUUAUUGUAAAUACUGGUGAACAGUGGUUAAUAAAUAGUUUUAUAUUCCUUUAUGCAAUUAUUAGACUUUUUUCUUUAUUUGAUAUGCCUUUACAGUAGAAAUAGAAAUGCCCACACUCAUUGGAUUAUCUUUGUUUAUAAGUUAGAUGAUACCAGUAAGGCAUUACAGUACAUAUCCUAGAUCUUUUGAGCUUACGAGUUUUAAACUUGAAUAUGUAUUUCCACAGGAAUGUUUCCACAGUUGGGAAAUAAAAGUUUCAUGUGAUGCCUAGGGUCAAUUGUCUCAUUAAAAUGAGGUUUUAAAUUCUG